UUUUUUUUUUUUUUUUUUUUUUUUGAGACAGCGUCUGGCUCUGUCGCCCAGGCUGGAGUGCAGUGGCGCAAUCUCGGCUCACUGCAAGCUCCGCCUCCUGGGUUCACGCCAUUCUCCUGCCUCAGCCUCUCAAGUAGCUGGGACUACAGGAGCCCGCCACCGCUCCCGGCUAAUUUUUUGUAUUUUUAGUAGAGACGGGGUUUCACUGUGUUACCCAGGAUGGUCUCGAUCUCCUGACCUCAUGAUCCACCCGCCUCGGCCUCCCAAAGUGCUGGGAUUACAGGCGUGAGCCACCACGCCCGGCCGGAAAUUUUUUUUGAGAUGGAGUCUCUGUCUGUUGCCCAGGCUGGAAUGCAGUGGCACAAUCGUGGCUCACCUCCCAGGUACAAGCGAUUCUGCUGCCUCAGCCUCCCAAGUAGCUGGGAUUACAGGUGUGCACCACCACCCCCGGCUAAUUUUUGUAUUUUUUGUAGAAACGGGGUUUCACCACGUUGGCCAGCCUGGUUUUGAACUCCUGACCUCAAAGUGAUCUACCUCACAAAGUGCUGGGAUUACAGGCGUGAGCCACCACACCUGGCCUAUUAUAAUUUUUUUAUAUGGAGAAGGACCAAAAUAAUCCAAAGAUGUAACUCUUUGCAUUUUGGGUUUUUUAGUUUUACUUUUUUUCACAUACAGGUAUGGGCAUGUGCACGCACGCACUCUGUCUCUCUUCUUUUCUUUUUUUUUUUUUUAAUUAAAAAACCCACCGGCCAGUUGUGGUGGCUCACGCCUAUAAUCCCAACACUUUGGGAGGCCAAGGCUGGCAGAUCACAAGGUCAAGAGAUUGAGACCAUCCUGGCCAACAUGGUGAAACCCUGUCUCUACUAAAAAUACAAAAAUUAGCUGGGCAUGAUGGCGCACGCCUGUAGUCCCAGCUACUCAGGAGGCUGAGGCAGGAGAAUUGCUUGAACCCAGGAAGUGGAGGUUGCAAUGAGCCUAGAUCGGGCCACUGCACUCCAGCCUGGUGAUGGAGCAAGACUCCAUCAAAAAAAAAAAAAAAAAAACCUAUCUCCUGCACAGUCUCUCCCUUUUCUUAUGCCUCUCCUGACUCCUUUUUUUUUUCCAAACUUGGAAUCAUACUAUAAGUUAUUUUAUAAUUUGCUUGUUUCACCCUAACAGCCUGAUCCUUUUCCUUUGUCAUUAAGUAUUCUCCUACAACCUGGUUUCUAAUGGCUACAUAGUACUCCAACAUACAUAUGUUAUUUAAUGGACAUAAUCAGAACCAUGUUGCAAGGCAUUUAGGUUAUCUUUAUUUUUGUACUAUUUUAUGCAUGUAUAAUACUGUUGAAUAUCCUUUAUAUGAAUUUUUGUAUACAUUUCUUUUUGCCUUAGGGCAGAUUCCUGCAAGUAGACUUUGGGAGUCAAAGCAUAUACACAUUUUAAUGCUUUUGCUAGCUAUUCCAUUACUCGGUAAAUUAAUAUUUACGUUUCCACCUGCGGUGUUUAAGAGCUCCUAUUUUUUUUUUUCUUUUUUCUUUUUUUUUUUGAGAUGGGGUCUCAAUCUGUCUCCCAGGCUGCAGUGCAGUGCAGUGGCAUGAUCUCAGCUCACUGCAACCUCUGCCUCCCGGGUUCAAGCAGUUCUCCUGCCUCAGCCUCCCAAGUAGCUGGGAUUACAGGCGCCUGCCACCACACCCCGCUAAUUUUUGUAUUUUUAGUAGAGACACAGUUUCACCUUGUUGGCCAGGCUGUUCUCAAACUCCUGACCUCAGGUGAUCCGCCCACCUCAUCCUCCCAAAGUGCUGGGAUUACAGGCGUGAGCCACCGCACCCACCAAGAGUUCCUACUUUUCUGAACAGUGCCCUUUAUUAUAAUUUUUUAAACUAAUUUUUUCUAAUUAAAAUGUUUAGAAUUAUAUAUGAGGAAAUCAUUUGGCAGCCUUUAAGGCUUGUCUAUUUAGCCUAUCAAGCAUAACAAAUUCAAGAACUUUUUGGACCAGGUGCGGUGGCUCACACCUGUAAUCCCAGCACUUUUGGGAAGCUGAGGUGGGCGGAUCACUUGAGGUCAGGAGUUUGAGACCAGCCUGGCCAGCAUGGUGAAACCCCGUCUGUACUAAAAAGACAAAAAUUAGCUGGGUAUGGUGGCACUUGCUGUAAUCCCAGCUACUUAGGAGGCUGAGGCAGGAGAAUCGCUAGAACCCGGGAGCCGAGAUUGCACCAUUGCACUCCAGCCUGGGCAACAGAGUGAGACUCCAUCUCAAAAAAAAAAAAAAAAAAGAAAAAAAAAAAACAACUUUUUAGGCCAGGCGUGGUGGCUCACACCUGUAAUCCCAGCACUUUGGGAGGCCGAGGCGGGCGGAUCACGAGGUCAGGAGAUCGAGACCAUCCUGGCUAACAUGGUGAAACCCUAUCUCUACUAAAAAAAAAAUACAAAAAAAAUUAGCCGGGCCUGUUGGCCUGCGCCUGUAGUCCCAGCUACUUGGGAGGUUGAAGUAGGAGAAUGGCGUGAACCCGGGAGGCUGAGCUUGCAGUGAGCCGAGAUCGCACCACUGCACUCCAGCCUGGAUGACAGAGCAAGACUCUGUCUCAAAAAAAAAAAAAAAAAAAAAAAAAGCCUUUUUGACUCAUUAGAGAAUAAAUGUAGGUUAAUUGUAGAUCAUUUAGAUAUUAUGAAAGCAUAAAGUGAAAAGUAUCAUUAAGCAUCCUUUUAAGAUGGGUGAGGUUUUACGUGCAAUUUUGUGUCACGCUUUUUUUACUUAAUUUAUCUCAUGUAUUUUCUAUUACAUUAAAAUCUUCCUUAUUAAUGGCUUCAUAAAAUCCAUUGUAUGGCAAUAUUAUGACUUACCCAACCAUUCCUCUUAUAUUGUCUACCUUUUUUUUGGUCUCCUAAUUCUUGCUGUUAUAAGUAACCCUGUGAUGGGUAUUAUGUGCAUAAAACUUUGUUUGCAUUUUUAUUAUCCCUGAGUACAUAUGGAUUCCAUGAAAUAAAAUUCAUGUGUCACAGCAGGAGUGAACAUAUUCAAGUAUCUCAGUGCAUAUAACCAAAUAACUUUCCAGAAAAGCUACACCAGUUACACUUAACACCCGCAGUGUAUGAGCAUGCCCGUGUGAUGGGCACUUCAACAGCAUGGAGUACCCCUGUUGUGUUUGCUGGCCAGGCGUGGUGGCUCACGUCUGUAAUUCCAGCACUUUAGGAGGCCAAGGCGGGCGGAUCACCUGAGGUCAGAAGUUCGAGACCAGCCUGACCAACAUGAUGAGACCCUGUCUCUACUGAAAUUACAAAAAUUAGCUGGGCAUGGUGGUAGGCUCCUGCAAUCCUAGCUACUCGGGAGGCUGAGGCAGGAGAACCGCUUGAACCCGGGAGGCGGAAGUUGCAGUGUGAGAUCACACCAUUCCACUCCAGCUUGGGUGACAGAGUGAGACUCUGUCUCAAAAAUAAAAAAUAAAAAUAAAAGAUGCUAAUUUACCAAGUGAAAAAUAAUCAGGAAGUUUUUCUUGAAUGAAUAAUAAAUAGAGAUAGGACUAUGAAUUAAGUAGCAUUCUGUCAUUGUUUUAUUAGUAAUAUAACUAUUACAAAUGUGAUCAAAUUUUUUUUUAUUAAAAGUCACUUUUUAAAGUCAACUUACCCCCCAAAAAAGUGUAUUAUUUUUUUCCCCCAAUAUAUGGGGAAUUUAAUUUUUUUCUGUCAUUUUGAAAAAUCAAUGCCAAGAGAUAAUACCAUAUUGAGAUUUUUGACCAAAUGUUAACAGCGUAAAUUGCCCUGGUUCAAGACCUCCACUCCUUGGUUCUUGGUCCCUUCAGUUUGUGGUAUGAAUAAACAUCAUUUGUAAUUAUUUGACUAAGUCAUUUAAAAUCCCUGUUCUUCAGUUUAAUAUACUGUUUUGCUCCUCCUUUCUCAUUGAGGUACUGUAUGAAUUUAAGGGCCAUACGAAGUAUUUGUCCCUUCUUAAAAGAUAGGCACAGGAUAUAGACUCGGUAAUAAAAUGUGGUUUGGGUUUCUAGUAUUUUUUUAUGCUUCCAGGUACCCAGAACCGCAAAUUUUACUUUGAGCUCCUCAGAAGAAAGGUGCUCCAGGCAUCUGAGAGAAUACCGUUGGGGUGAUACUUACAAAUUUGUAAGCUAACACUGAAAUCUUAAAACUUCCGAAAAUAUUAAUGCAUUUGUAUGACUUAUUUUUCAACUGAGUAUGUCAAAGUACUUUAUGAACAAGUGUUGUCCCUAGUUUGUACUGAUGGGGAAACUGAGGCAUGGGGUGAUAAGGUGACUGGCCCAAGGUUACAAAAUGAGUUAUUGACAACUCCGGAAAUAGAAGAUUUUUUAAAUUCCCAUACUAGAUACAUGUGGGCAUUGACAUUCAAAGCUUCCCUCAUGCUAUUUCCUUUAGUCCUGUCCUUUGGGGAUUGCCUCUGAGGGUGAGAGGGUAGUUCAGGUUUCCGGGCUUGUUCAGCCUUUAGUCUCUGUAGAGGCUUCCAGCAAGCUGACAAGUUACUGCCAAAAGUGAGACAGAUGGUAUUUUUUAUGAUGUUGUCCUUAGUUGGAGACUGCUAGUGAUUCUCCUCCUCAGGCUACUCUUUGAAAAGCUGUAAGGUGGUAUCAGCUUUAUCGUGGUUGGCUGAGGAAGGAUUUGUACAAGUAAAUGUUCUCUGCCUUAUUGUCAUUCCUAGGGCCGUCUGGUCUUAUAGUACCCUGAAGGUGAGGGAUUAGAUUAUGCUCUGAAUUUGUAUGCCCAUAGUUUGAGGAAAUGUUUUACUUGAGUUUUCUGUGUGUUGAGAUGAAAGUCUCCCAGGCUAAAGAUUUCUGAACUGCACGCAAUGUCUGAAGAAGCGCUUGAAAGGCACUUUAUUUCUCCCAGGUCCCCAACCAUGGGUUUAGGUUUUUAUGCCAGAAAGGGGACCUUCAUGAACAAAGACCCCCAAGACCUAGAGAGAAGAGGAAGUCUGAAAGAGGGAGGUUUGAAUUCAGCCUUCAGGAAUGAAGAGGGCAGACAGAGCAGGAGGCUCAGGCAAGGGAGUCAGGAACCACAGACCAGAAACAUGGACUUGGAAAGGUUUUCAUGUAAUUGAAAUGAAGCUAUUGAUCCAUCCAUUUUAAAAGAAUUUGAAAAAUUCAUUAAAAUACUUAAUUAGUGGCAUCCACUAAUUAAUAAAAGCAUAGGGAGUGGCAUCUUUAACCAAAAAUGAAAAUGAAGAAACAGACUCCAGCCCAGGGACCAGGGGCGAUUAUGAGGGACAUGGUGCCUCAUACAGCCAAGAUGAUCCAAGAGGCAUCAUCUUUAAUGAAGCUUUAACACCUGGCAGCCUGCUCAUUGUGUUGUUUAAGAGGUAAGUAUGAACUGGUUUUGUUUGUAGCUUUUGUGUGGAAUCAGGUAGUGCUGUCUGCAGAGUGUAAACCUUUAUUUCUUUAAGUAGGAAUAACAGAUAAAGUAAUUCUAUAUUAAAUCCCAAGAGUUUUAUUCUAAAUUGGUAAUGUGACUUUCAUCUCUCGAGUUUUUUCAAAUCGUUUUUAAUUUGUGGUUGAGUCUUCACGAACUUCUUGUCAUCAGGCAAUAGUUGAUUCCCCUUUUUUGAAAGCUUUCAAUUUCAUUUAUCCUUAGUGUUGAAAAGUGUCAGAAAAUUGAAAUGGACACAGAUGAUUGUAUCUGCCCUCCCUUUCAGGAAAGCCAUGUUGACUUUAAAAUAUCAAAAAAGAAAGUUCAGUUAUGAUUGCAGGGGGUAAUGAUAGUUUGAUCCACAAACUAUUUGCAGUGUAAAAGUGAAAUACCUUAGCUGACUUAGUUCAUUUUUGAAAGUUUUGAAUAGCUAAAACAAAGUUGGCAAAUAGGCUCAUAGAGUAGUUACAGAGUAAGACUAAAUUCAUAUUUGAUGCAGAUUCCUCUCUACCUCCCAUUCUGGGAGGAUUUAGUUUUACUGUUUGGUGUUUAGGAUAAUGAUUGUUCUGUUUUUCUCACCCUACUAUGUGAAUAUAUAUUCUGUUAGAGAUGGGCUGUUAUCUGCAAUGUGGACUCAAUACCAUGGGCUUGAGUUUGGUUAGUUCAUCAUUAGAGAUUUUUUUUCAGCAGUUGGUUUACUUUAUGAGAAAGGAUCAUGAGUUUAAUUUUCCCACUGAUAUAUUUGUGUUCUCAUUGCUGAGAUAUAAGUUUCUUAAUGAUUUGUUACCUUUUUCUAUUUUCCUAGACUAGUAUUAAAAUUUUGAUGGCAUAUGGGUUUGGUUCCACUUGUAGAGAAUAAAUGUUCACAACUUACUGGUAUUAGCACACACACAUCACAUGCAGAAAUGGUGUUUUCUUGCCACUUACUCUUUCUCAUAAGAUGCUUAUAUUCCUGUGGGCAUUUGUCUUCCACACUACAGCACAUAAUUUGAUGAAACUGAUUUUCUGUGCAAGAGCUUGUGUUUCUCCAACUCUGGUUUUAUGGACCACUUUUCAUUGGUAUAUAGGAGGCGGUUAAAACGUGGUGGUAGAAUGCAGGUUUUAGGUUAGCUGGGUGUGAAGAAUCCCAGGUCUUUGGGAUAGUCUUGGCAAGUUACUCAACUCCUCUAAGUUAGUUUCUUGAUCUGUCAGAUGACAGUAAACCUCAGAGUUGUGAAAAUUAAAUGGAUAUAAUGUGUGUAAAGCACUUAGCAUAAUGCUUUAUACAUCGUAAAACUUUCAAAAAUAGGAGUAGUAAUUAUUACAAAGAAAUGUGAAGAAGAGUCCUAGUGGGCUGCAUGUUAAAAAUAGUUUUUAGUUAAUGAAAAUUAAAUCACAUCUUAGAUGUUUAUCAUCUGCAUGGUACUUUUCUGGUUGCUGCUUUAACCUUUGUAUAGUUGAAAGUCUGUAAACUUUCUAGUAUUCUUUGAUUUCUGGCCCAUUUCCCUCCUACCAUUCACGCUUAUAUUUUUUGGUUCAAGUCACCAUUCCUUGCAAAACUAAUUAAAUACAUUCCUAAAUACAUAAUAUUGCCAAUAUUCAUUCACAUCCACCACGUCUAGAUCCAAGUCUUCAUCUUCUUUAUGCUGGUCUAAUUUUUGCUGAGCCUUAGAAGCAAAGACAGACUCCGGGGGUUGAUAUGGGACCUCCAGAAUGGGGAUUGCACAGAAUAAUCUUAUUUUUCCUCUAUUCUUCUAGUCUGUUAUGUUCUGAACCCACACAUGUUUUCGGAAGGACCAGAUGGCUGACACUGGCUAAUGGGAACCAAAAGACGAGUGAAAGUAACCUGGUUGUCACAUACCCCCAGCUUAGAGGUGCUUCACCCUGCCCCAAGGUCAAUUUCUUUUUUCUCUAGAGACUUUACCCCAUUAUAUCAAAAACCUUUACUACAGCCUGACUUUAUCUGAUGUUAGAGUAUCAUUAAGUCAAGCAGCAGCAUUUAUUGAGUGAAAAAAGAUUGUACACAGGACUGGAAGAGAAGCAUCUGCCUUUAAAAUACAGUAGAAGGCCGGGCAUGGUGGCUCAUGCCUGUAAUUCUAGCACUUUGGGAGGCCAAGGCAGGUGGAUUGCCUGAGCUCAGGAGUUCGAGACCACCCUGGGCAACAUGGUGAAACCCUGUCUCUCCUAAAAAAAAAAAAAAAAAAAUUACAAAAAAUUUGCCGGGCAUGGUGGUGCACACCUGUAGUCCCAGCCACUCUAAAGGCUGAGGUACAAGAAUUGCUUGAGCCCAGGGUCAGAGGUUGCAGUGAGUGGAGAUCGCGCCGCUGCGCUGCAGCCUGCGCGACAGAGCGAGACUAUGUUUUUUUUAAAAAAAAAAAAAAAAAGGAAUUAGAACCUUGUGGUUUAGAGCUGGGAUUUUUAGAGUCAUGGGUCUGGGUUCAAAUCUAGCUCCUUCACUCAUGAGCUCCUUGAAAAUGAGCAAGUUGCUUACUCCAAGCCUCAGUUUCUCAUUGUAAAAUGAGAAGAAUAAUAAUACAUUCUUCACAUUUGAUAUACAAAUGGAUGAAAUAUUAUGGAUAAAUUAUUUACUGUGCCAGGCACUGUGCUAAAUAGCCAACAGAUAUUAGCCUUCGUUUUUCUUAGUGAAGAGCUCAUAAUCAAAAGAGAAGGUAAGCACAAAGACAAAAACAAGACUUAAAAAGCUACAGAAACAUGACUGGGCACAGUGGCUCACGCCUGUAAUCCCAGCACUUUGGGAGGCUGAGGCGGCCAUAUCACAAGGUCAGGAGUUUGAGACAAGCCUGACCAACAUGGUGAAACCCCGUCUCCACUAAAAAUAUAAAAAUUAGCUGGGCGUGGUGGCGUGUGCCUGUAAUUCCAGCUAUUCAAGAGGCUGAGGCAGGAGAACUGCUUGAACCUGGGAGGUGGAGGCUGCAGUGAGCCAAGAUUGUGCCUUUGCACUCCAGCCUGGGCAACAGAGCGAGACUCCAUCUCAAAAAAACAAAAACAAAAAGCGUAAAAUUGAAUAGAAGUGCUAAAGCUAAAGAAAGUCCUAAAAUAAUUGGAAUAGGCAAGUUUCUGAGGCUUCAUGAAAGAGGUAAUUCUCAAGCAUAUGGAAGAAGAUUGAUAUAAUUCAACUUGUGUAGUCAAGGUGUUCCAGGUUUAGAGAGUGACAUAAAGAUACUUAGGAGUCGUUAUAGACUUCUAAACAAAAAAAUGAUUUAGUAGCUGACUUUUCCUGACACAAUGCAAAAGACAAGUUGACUAAGUAAAAAUAGCUCUAGCCUAGAAUUACAUAAAUUAAUCCAAAUGGUAGAGACAGCCCUGAAGGCCCAGCAAAUGAGAAAACUGCAGAACUUGGCAGUAGACCCAGUGGGUAACCAAUAAGAUAUAGUCAGAAGUGAUUACAAAGGUGUUGGGAGCAAAUUAGAUGGUCAAGGGAUCCGGAAGAGAGAAAUCAUGAGGUAGGUUUUCUUCUUUGAAGGUGGGGAAAGAUCAAGUGCAGACUGAGCUGUGGCCAACGUUUGCAGACCAGGAAUCCACACUAGCUCUAAUCAGAGAGCCCUUGGUGUGCGGGAACUGCCAGUUUGCCGACGUGAAAAGAGUCCCAGACUGGGUAAUGGUGAGCCCUGAAGUCGCACCCCAGCUCUGCCACUCAGUGAGCACGGCAACAUCCCUAAUCCUGACCAGCCAUGGAGAGGUUCGGUUCUUACAAGGAAAAUGAGUGAAUGUGGGAAUGGCUCACCACAUUGUGAAAACAAAACUCACAUCCUGCUGAUGGUUGGCUGAGGACUGUCAUGUCCACAUACAAAGAAAAGCAUGUGGCACAGUUUUAGGACAAAGUUGCCACCAACUACUUGGGAAACAAAAGAAGUGUCCUGUGUAUGUAGCCAGCCUCCUCCUAGAAAGAUAGGAGUCUACUUUGAGAAGUCUCCCUACCUCUUUCAGUGCCUGUUGGCACAAAGCAAAGUGGUUUCACCUGAAGAGAAGACAAAGUUGAUCCUUAGUUUGCAAAAUCCACCUAACCUUUGCUAAGCAUGAACCUCAUUGCUUUCUCUUUAAUGUUAGUGAAGCUGGAUGUCAAAAUGGUACCAACCAGUAUUUUCUUUGCUCUCUUCUAGAUAUGGUUUUGUGGAGUUUGAUGAUCUGCGUGAUGCAGAUGAUGCUGUUUAUGAACUGAAUGGCAAAGACCUUUGUGGUGAGCGAGUAAUUGUUGAGCAUGCCCGCGGCCCACGGCGAGAUGGCAGUUACGGUUCUGGACGCAGUGGAUAUGGUUAUAGAAGAAGUGGCCGAGAUAAAUAUGGCCCUCCUACUCGCACAGAGUACAGACUUAUUGUGGAGAAUUUGUCAAGUCGGUGCAGCUGGCAAGACCUAAAGGAUUAUAUGCGUCAGGCAGGAGAAGUGACUUAUGCAGAUGCUCACAAGGGACGCAAAAAUGAAGGGGUGAUUGAAUUUGUAUCUUAUUCUGAUAUGAAAAGAGCUUUGGAAAAGUUGGAUGGAACUGAAGUCAAUGGGAGAAAAAUCAGAUUAGUUGAAGACAAGCCAGGUUCCAGACGACGCCGGUCCUACUCCAGAAGCCGGAGUCAUUCAAGGUCUCGCUCUCGAAGCAGACAUUCCCGUAAGAGCAGAAGCCGAAGUGGCAGCAGCAAAAGCAGUCAUUCUAAGAGUAGAUCUCGGUCCAGGUCGGGCUCCCGCUCCCGGAGCAAGAGCCGGAGCCGGAGCCAGAGUCGGAGCCGGAGCAAGAAAGAGAAAAGCAGGAGCCCCAGCAAGGAAAAGAGCCGCAGCCGCAGCCAUAGCGCUGGCAAGAGCCGCAGCAAGAGCAAAGACCAAGCUGAAGAGAAGAUCCAAAACAAUGACAAUGUCGGGAAACCCAAGAGCCGGAGUCCUAGCAGGCAUAAAAGUAAGAGCAAAAGUCGGAGCAGGAGUCAGGAGAGGAGAGUGGAGGAGGAGAAGCGAGGGAGUGUGAGCAGGGGCAGGAGCCAGGAGAAGAGCCUCCGCCAGAGUCGGAGCCGGAGCAGGAGCAAAGGGGGCAGCAGGAGCCGGAGCAGGAGCCGCAGCAAGAGCAAGGACAAGAGGAAGGGCAGGAAGAGAAGCAGAGAGGAGAGCCGCAGUCGCAGUCGCAGCCGCAGCAAGAGUGAGAGGAGCAGAAAGCGAGGCAGCAAGCGAGACAGCAAGGCGGGCAGCAGCAAGAAGAAGAAGAAGGAAGACACUGACCGCUCCCAGUCCAGAUCUCCAUCCCGCUCCGUGUCAAAGGAGCGGGAACAUGCCAAGUCUGAAUCCAGCCAGAGGGAAGGUCGAGGAGAGAGUGAGAAUGCUGGCACCAAUCAGGAGACCCGGUCCAGGUCGAGAUCCAAUUCCAAAUCGAAACCAAACCUUCCAUCAGAAUCACGCUCCAGAUCAAAGUCAGCUUCAAAAACCCGAUCUCGGUCCAAGUCUAGAUCCAGGUCUGCUUCCAGAUCGCCCUCCCGAUCUAGAUCUAGGUCCCACUCAAGGUCCUAACUGGCUAUGGCCACAGCUGGAACUACCCGAGAAGUCUUUUGUACAUGUUUGGUAGCCGUAGCACAAGUGAUUGGAGUAGAACAUGUCACUGCUGUACAUUUUUAACUCCCCUAAUGGUGUGUCUAUAAUUGUUAAAUCUAAGUGCUUCCUCUCAGUAAAGCCUCCUGGCACCAGGCCUUCCUGCUCGACUGAAAAAAAUUUUCUCUUUGAAAAUCCCCUUUUACUCAUGGCCCACAGUAGAAUAUCCAAAACGCCUUGGCUUUCAGGCCUGGCCUUUCCUACAGGGAGCUCAGUAACCUGGACGGCUCUAAGGCUGGAAUGACCACAUAGGUAGGUAUGGUGAGUUCAACCAUUUUUGCUCUUGAAUUGAUGCCCUUCGAUGUAUGCCAUUUAGUGAAAGUGCUAAGUCUUAAGUUUCCUACCACUUUGGUUUCAUAUUUUUGGACUUAACAAAGUUGUGAAUAGCACAGUCGAGGAAAAUUGAUACCUGCAGUAACCCAUAGGAAAUAAACUGUAGAGUUCCAUAUUCUGGUAUUGUGAUUAUAUUGUUUUAUAUUAAAAAAGAAAAGAAAAGAAUUUUUUUUAAUUUUAUUUUUCCCCGUCUUGCAAAGUAUAGUGACCCCUGUUUCCAUUAAAUUUGAAUAAAGACUAUUUUUGCUUGACAAAA